GCAGAGCCGGGCCGGCGCACGAGGCAGCCAGCGCGGCCAUGACGGCGGAGAAGGCGCUGCCCCUGGGCAAUGGGAAGGCUGCUGAGGAGGCGCGGGAGUCCGAGGCGCCGGGUGGCGGCUGCAGCAGCGGGGGCGCGGCGCCCGCGCGCCACCCGCGCGUCAAGCGCGACAAGGCGGUCCACGAGCGCGGCCACUGGAACAACAAGGUGGAGUUCGUGCUGAGCGUGGCCGGGGAGAUCAUUGGGCUGGGCAACGUGUGGCGCUUCCCCUACCUGUGCUACAAGAACGGAGGAGGGGCAUUCCUGAUUCCCUACGUGGUGUUUUUUAUUUGCUGUGGAAUUCCUGUUUUUUUCCUGGAGACAGCUCUGGGGCAGUUCACAAGUGAAGGUGGCAUUACGUGUUGGAGGAAAGUUUGCCCUUUAUUUGAAGGCAUUGGCUAUGCAACACAGGUGAUUGAGGCCCAUCUGAAUGUGUACUACAUCAUCAUCCUGGCAUGGGCCAUUUUUUACCUGAGCAACUGCUUCACUACUGAGCUACCCUGGGCUACCUGUGGGCAUGAGUGGAACACAGAGAAUUGUGUGGAGUUCCAGAAACUGAAUGUGAGCAACUACAGCCAUGUGUCUCUGCAGAAUGCCACCUCCCCUGUCAUGGAGUUUUGGGAGUAAGUGGAGAAGAACUUGUCUCCCUUGGCCUGUGGGGGCUCUGUCCUGGUUCUGCUCAGUUGGUCUUGCCCCUAUUCCUGGAAAAAGCCUGAUCCUUCUUGCAGCCUGGCACUUCCUGGCUUCUGUGAGCAUUCGACAGCUUCGGAAGCAAGAGUGCAGAUCUUCAGAGGUUUCCCAAAGGGGCAGCUGAGAGAAAUGUUUUCUUGUUCUUUGAUAACAUGUCAGCAUGCAUAGUGGGUUAUUAGGGCAGGAAGUACUUGGUGAAAGGAUAGACAGUUUAAAAAUUCAUUUUGAGCAAAAGAGGAGAUGCAGCCUGUUUGCAAUAAGCUAAGUCAAGAGUGUAUUUAGCCUGGAAAGCAUAAGUCUCUAGAGGGGAUAGGUUAGCUUUCUUUCAGUAGCUGAAGUGUCAUAUGGAAAAGAAGGAGAUCAAAUUUAAUGGAUAGAGAUUAUAAAGAGGCAGGUUUCAAAUGUGCGUAGGGAAGAACUUGGUCUCAUAGCAUAGCAUUAUCUGGAAGCACUUCAGAAGGUUGUGAGCACCCAUCCCUGGAAGUUGACCAGUAUAGGGUUGCCAAUCAUUGUUGGGGGUGUGUCUGAAUCCACUGAAAUUAUAAGUAGUACUUGUGUGGUUGGGCAUUUUCCCAGAAAUUGGCAUAGUUUUAUCAGAGUUCCAAAGGAUCUGUGACCCUUACAGGGCUGCUAUGUGUGGUUGUGUACAUUGCACACUGAACAACCCAAGGGGCCAUAAUUUACAUUAUGAAAUAUACAUUCCAGAAUUGUGUGGUGCACGACCUGUAUAACCAUACACAGUGGCCCUGACUUGCAAGUUUGUUUUAAAGGUAGAAGGAUCCCUUGCCCCAGGUAUUGGAAAGAAGUUUCCUGUAUGGGUCAAAGGCUGGACUAAAUGCUUUCUGAAGCUUUUCAAUCUAAAAAGUCCUGGCUUCAUUGAAGAAGCCUCCCUUACUCUGAUGGUGAUUAAUAGUAGUAUAUGUGUGUGUGGUGGGGCAGUGGUUUAUGAGUGAUUUUUAUUUUUUUCCCAGAUACCAUUCGUCUCCUGCCUUCUCUAGAGGUCAUUAUGCUGAAUUUAGAUUUACCACUCUCAUAUAAAUCUUCAUACUUUUCAUAUAUAUAUGCCCCAAAUAGCACCUAGGUCUUUCUUGCAUAUUUUUCAAAUUUGUGAUACUGGCAUCCAUUAUUUACAUUUUUUAUAACAACUUUAUUUCUUUGCUCAAUAUUGGUUCUUAGAUGUAUCCAUAUUGGUACAUGUAGCUUUGGUUCUUUCAUUUUUCUAUCAGAGUAUUUCAUUGUAUGAAUGGCCUGUGUUGUAUUUAUCCAGGUCCUCUUGGUCCUCUUGAUGGGCAUUUAGGCUGUUGCCCAUUUCUCACUAUUAUUAAGCACACUGAGUGAAUGUCUAGUCUGUGCUUCCUUGAGUGGAAUUGCUGGGUUGUAGCAUACAUGCGUUGUCAGUUUUAUCAUAUAACGUAAAAUUACUUUAGAAAGAAAUUAAUCUAGGCCAGGCAUGGUGGCUCACACCUGUAAUUCCAGCACUUUGGGAAGCCGAGGUGGGCGGAUCACCUGAGGUCAGGAGUUUGAGACCAGCCUGGCCAACAUGGUGAAACCCUGUCUUUACUAAAAAUACAAAAAUUAGCUGGGUAGUGGUUCAUGCCUGCAAUCUCAUCUACUCAGGAGGUUGAAGCAGGAGAAUCACUUGAACCUGGAAGGCGAAAGUUGCAGUGAGCCGAGAUCGGCGCCACUGCACUCCAGCCUGGGUGACAGAGCGAGACUGUCUCAAAAAAAAAAAAAAAAAUUAAUUUACACUCCAAACAAGAGUUUGUGAGAAUUUCUGCAGCUUCACAUUUUGGACAGCACUUGGUCUGUUCAGUUUUUGUUUUGCCAGUGUAAUGGGCAUUAAAUGAUAACUUACUAUUUUAAAUUCACAUUUCUCUAAUUACUUGUGAGGUUAAGCACCUUUUCAUGUUUUGUUUUGUCUGUUUUUUGCUAUUUGAUUUCUGUACCUGUGAACUUCAGGUUUACAUUCGUUUCUAUUUGGAUAGUUUGUCUUUUCUUACAGAUAGAAAUUGUUAAUACAUUCUAGAUAUUAUCUUUUCCCAAUGUGUGGCUUUUCUUUCUUAUUUAUGGUGUACAGAAGUUUCCAUUUUAUUGAAGUCGAAUUCGUCGAUUUUUCUUUUGGGUUUGCACAGUUGGUGUCUUAUUUAAGAUAUAUUUCCCUACCCCAAAGUUGAAAAAAUUUUCCAUAUUUUCUUCUAAGAGUUUUACAGUUUUUUUUCAUAUUUAGGAAUAUAAUCCAUCUGGAAUUUUAUGUUUUUAAUGUUGUAUUAGGUAGAAAUCCAGGUUUUAAUAUAUAAAUAACCUAUUUUCCCAGUAGGACUUACUGAUCAUUCAUUCUUUUCUGAUUUAUAAUGCCAUCUUCUGUACAUAAUUUCCUUUAAGCACAAGUCUGUGUUUGGGCUCUCUGUUCUGUUCCACUGGUCUCUUUGUCUAUCUCUGUGCCCAUACCACACCUAUAGUUUUACUGUAAGCCUUGAGCCUGUAAGGCAAGUCUCCCACUUUGUUCUUUUCCAAAAUUGUUUUAGUCUUCUAAAUGAAUUUCAGAAUCAGUUUGUUGAAUUAAACAAGAAUAGCAAUAAAAAAACAAAAUAACUGUGUGGGAAUUUUGAUUAAAAGUCUAUUGAACUCAUAGGUUAGUUUGAGAGAAUUUGACAUCUUUAUGAUUGAACCUGUCUAUGGACAUGGUAUAGCUAGUUCUCCAUUUGUUUAUGUCUUUUAAAUUGCCUUAUAGAGUAGUGCUACUUAAAUGUGGUCUACAGAGUAGCAGCAUUUUAAUCACCUGGUUACCUACCCCAGGCCUACUGAAUCAUAGUCUCAAACAGAGCAUCUGUUAGAUAUGUGCUUGAAAGGAGACUUCUGGGCUGGGUGGGCCUGUGUGGUCUUUCCCAGUCCCAUUGGGUUGAGGUUUCCUGGAAGAAUGUCAGAGACUUGUAUUGGACCUGCACAUUUGGGGGUCUGCAGAACAGUUUCUUUCACCUUUAGAGAAUUCACUCUGAAACUCCAGACUGGACAAGGUCUCUGUGUUAGUUACUGUUGUUUUUGCACCACUCAUUUCCUUUGUAACAUAUAUGGAAAACCUUAAUUAAAUCAUUAUUUGUAUAAUGUAUUUGUUCAUUGUCUGUAUUCCCCAAUAGACAGUCAUGAAGCAGAACCUUGUCUGGUUUUACUUAUCAUUGCCAGGCUAUGGAAGGCCCUCAGUUAAUAUUUAUAAACUAGAUGGAUGGAUGAAGAAGGCAGACAGGCAGGCAAUAUGUCCUAGAAAAUAUUAUAUGAGAAGAGUCAAAGUGGGCUCUGGCAAGAACACCUGCUGUCAUUAAGCCUCUCACCCAACAGCAUUGAUUAAUUCCAGGAUCCCUUUGCAAUAUCCAUAUUAUCCAUUCAUUUGAACACCAAGGGCAGGCAAGGGCAGUUUGUGUGCAUCCUCAUCGGUAUAGACCAUCCUGCCAGCUACUUGGUUACUCAAGAUGAAAGUUCAUGGGCAAAUGAACCCAUGGUUCUAGUUUUCUAUUCAGAUUGCAUCUCUGUCUGUAUCAUCCAUGUGGUGUUGAAUCCUGUAUCCUAAAAGUACUCAAAUACUAGUGGGACACGCACCCCUUCAUACAGUUAUACUUUUGUCAGACACCUCUAAUUCCUCUUUGCCCCUGAGCUGAGAUUAGAAUAUAGAGAUUGUGUGAGAUGUUCAUAUCAUCCUAUGAAAAGCUUUUGAGCCACAUAAGUUUGAGAAUGGAUGAAAGCUAUGUCCUUCAGUGAGAAUAUCCAUUUACCUUUGCUGAACCCAAAUUUCCAAACUUAUUUUCCUAUGGAAUAAAUUAGAAUCCCUUCCCUCUCUCUGCCCCUGCCCCAGUGUACUCCACCCCCUGAAUGCUAGCAUUCCACUAAAUGCAGUCUGGGAAACAUUUUGCUAGGAAUAAGUUCUUCCUUAAAUUCAGCCAAAAGUUGAUUUCUGGGGCUUUGACAGAGCAUACCUAAUUCCAUUUCUGUGUGACAGUACUCUUCAAGUAUUGGAUCAAGCUUCCUCAAAAACAUUCCUUCACCUCUCUUUGUUGUUUCCUUGUGUGGCUGGUUUGGUGGGCUCCAGUUGUCCUUUUCACACUGCCUCCAACUCCAGGGACUUCAGUCAGGGCCACAUUGCUCAGUCAAAGUAGACUGCCUAGGCUGUCUGCUAUUAUAGUUCAAUCAUUUGACAAACAUCUGAGCUCCUGGUACACAUAAGAAAAGCACGGUGUCUUAUUUAGGGGAAGUAAAGAUGGAAGAUGAGGUUCUAGUCUCUAGAAGCAGAGUUGAGACAAGCCCACAGAUUACCUUAAAAUCAUCCACAAGGCACUACUUCUCUGCCUGCAUCUGGCCAUGGCUUUGCCUUGACCAUGGGCACCUGGCCUGCCCACUCCCCAUCUUGAAGUGUCAAUUCCCUUUUCAGAUGUAAUUAAAAUUGCUGGCUUAGCCCACGAGAGAAGUUCAGGCCCUACAUCAGUCCUGGAUUCUGACUCUUAUGGGGGUCCUACAGGGCCAGGGAUGCUUGUCUUCCUAAUGUCAGACUUCAAAAUUAGGCCAUCCUCGUUUCCCUUAGUAACCCAUUAUGCAUCUGGCAUCCGUGCAUUUAUCUAAAUGUGUCUGCAGUUCUAAAUUUUGAGCCUGUACCCUCUGGUGGGAUUGAAUGCUAUUAAGUGCAUAACCAAUAUUGUGGCAUCAGAUGGACAUUGAUUCAUCUUCACUUCCCUUUCUCAAGCCCACAAAUCCCAUUAGUCCAGGGUUUGGGGAGCAACUCCAUUCUUGCUGUGUAUACAAUCAAAACUGUUUUUGCACGGUGUCCAUUCAAAAAACACAUGUUGAGCACAUAUUGUGUGCCGGGCCCAAAUUAAGCUCUAAGGGUAUUCAGUUCUAUUUAUUCAGAAGGAUGAGGCCUUGUUUUUCUGGUUUAUCUUCACUGGAGGAGUUUUGUUUUUAGUGUUUAUUUUUGAGUCACGUGAAUGUUUUAAUUGAUUUUCUUUGGACAUGAGAUUUGGGAUCAGAGGAACUAGAGUGAAGGUUGGUUCUUUCUGUGGGACUGGGGUGACUCCCUGCCUCUCUCCCAGGCCUAUCUUCCCCUCUGCACAUUACCCUCCUCCACACUGGCCUUCUUUCUGUUCUUUAGAUGUACGGGCCUUGUCCCAGGGUCAGUCUCUUGGCUUUUGCUUUUCCUUUUGCUAGAAGAUUUCUCACCAGAUCCUGUGUGUCUGGCUCCUUCUUAUCAUUGAGUCUUAAUUCAAAUGUCAGUGUCAUAUGGGGAGCCCUCCUUGACCAUGCCCAUGGAAUCCACACCCCAGUCCCUCUCAACCCCAUCACUCUUUCUUAAUGCCCCAUCACUCUUUCUUAAUAGUUCUUAUCUGAAAUCCUUGUAUAUUUAUUUGAUUAUUCUCUCUUUCUCCAUCAGAAUUUAAGUUCCAUGCUGGCAAGGACGAUGUCUGUUUUGUUCAUUAUUGUCUUGCCAGCACAUUCUAGGUGCUCAAUAAAUAUUUGUUGAAAUGAGUGAAUGGAAGACUGAAUGAAUGAAUGAAUAUUUCUUACCCCCUUGGAGCUCAGUGUCCACAUCUGUAAAUUGGAAAUGAUAACACCCACCUGAACACCCACCUGCAAGGCUGAGAAGAGAAUUGAAUAAGACUUCUCCUGUAGGAAGCCCAGCCCAUCUUAAGCUCUUUGGAAAGGUUUUAAUGUGUAAGAAGAUUUUUUGCAAUUGGUUCUCCCAUAUGUGAAAUGGGGUUAACCCUGUUCCUUGCCUUACCAACCUCUCCAGGCUGCUGUGAGGAUUAAAUGAAAUAACACAUUCUGAGAACUUUGAUGGGUCAUAAGUGGGGUGCCUGUGUUAGUUCUGGCUACUGGAGGCACAGGGUCCCUUCCAGCCUCAUCUCUACAGGUACAGAGUCAUGGUUGGGCCCAAGCUGCCAAGGCCUGUGCACAGUUGCUCUGUUUGCCUACAGUAGCCUUCAUGCCUCCUGAUUCAGCAUCAGAAGUGCCCUUGGGACCCUUUCCUAGGUCAGCACUGCAUGCUGUGUAGCAACAUCCAGUUCUGCUAGUUUGGAUUACCUGGCCCCACCAUACCCCCAACACAUUACCCCGUGGCUAAAGUGUAGAUGUUAGCGGCAAGUUCUAGAGCCCAGUUUAAGCAGCUGCCCCUUCCUCCUGUCAAGUGUGUGACCCUGGGCAACCUGAAGAGCCUCUGCCUGCUCCUCUGAAUAUGGGAUGAUGUAUGGUAAACGUACCCACCCCUUAGGCUUGUCAAGAGCAUGGAAUGAGAUGAUGCUUACAAAGCUCCUAGCAUGUGGUGAGUGCUAAUAAAUAGUAGCUGUUUUUACACAGGAGACUUUAUCCAGAUCUCUGCAAGUCUAUGUGGAUUCUUUUUAAGAUUCUUUAGAGAAGGCUCAUCAAGCAAGGCCUUGUUUCCCACUCACAGUAGGCAUGGUGAGCUUUCUUAGUGCAUUUUUUUCUUCACUUAAUUGUUCUUUUGACAUUUUUCUUAGUAAAUACUGGGUGCUGGGCAUCUUAUAAGUAGCCAGAAAGAUGAGUGGUGGGACACUGGCUCUCCAUGAAGAAGCACACAGCCCAGCAGGGGAAGCUGGGAAGUAGGAAAAAAAAAACAAAAAGAGUUUUUGAAUUACGAGGUAACAGAUAUAUCUGUAGGAUGCUUGCAGAGUGAGGCUGGGGAACCCUGGAUACCUGGACUUUGGGGAAGGCUACAUGGAGUUGGUGAUACUUUAGCUGGGUUUUGAAGGAUAAAUAGAAGUUCAUGCGGUUGGCCAUGGAGUGAGUAAAUGACAUACCAGGUGGAGAGAAUAAAAAAAGCAAGAGCACAGAGACCUGAAGUUGUGUGUUGCAGCUUAUAGAUUUUACCCACAAUGCUACUGCAUUUAGAUCCUAGGGGCUAAGGGGAGACUUUACUGAAGAGCAGGCAGGGGCCAGAGCAUCUAUGCACUCACAGGUCUUUAUUGAGCACCUACUAUAUGGCAGGUCUCAUUGUAGGUUCUGGAAUGCAACAUGAACAAAACAAAGACUCACCCUUAUGGAGCUGAGAGCACCAACAACCAAAUAAGCAGAAAAUAUUGGAUUAAGUUGAGAUCAGUUUCCUGAAGAAAAAGUCAGCAGGUUUAGGGGGCAGAAAGUGUUCAAGGGUCAGGGAGGGCCUCUCUGAGGAGGUGGCAUGUCAGCAAGGGAACUGAGAGAAGUGAGGGAGCAAGCCAUGUGGAGGUCCCAGGAGCUACAGGGCCGAGGGAGCAGCAGGGGUGGUGACCCCAUAGUGGGAGGCUGUUUGGGGAAUGGCAAGGCAGUCAAAGAGCCUGGAGAAGAGCAUGAAGGGCCUCUGUACCUUUCUAAAGGGUUUGCAGUGAUUCUGUGGGAUGCCUGCAAAUGUUCUAUUCCUAGAGUUGUGUGAUCAGGCCUGGGGAUAAGGCAGCCUCCCCAGGCUGCAGGUGGAGGCCCUGGAUGUGGUCCAGGUGCAGUAACCUAAGGCUCCUUCCUCCGGAGGUGGAAGCUGGGUGGUGGUGCCCUGCACUGUUGGGAAAGACAGGGUGGAAGCACUCUUGCCAUGCUUGGCCAUAGAAUACACUGAAGGGAAUAAGAGAAUGGUCUCUCUGAUGUAUUAAUUCCUCCACAGCCUCCCACUUGCUGUGAGGUCUUCUAAUCUCACAUGUCCUCAGUGAACUUGUUCUGAUGCAGGCAGAUGAGCAGCUCUUAAUCUGCCUGAACUCUCAAGUCCCCAUUUUUUUUUCUAAACAACAGCAACAGAAGCCAAUUUAGCAAUAACCCGCGGCACUGGGGCUGCACAUAAGUUUUGUCCCCAAAUCCUACUUCUGAAAGUUUAUUUUGCGAUAUGACCUCACUAGUUACACAGAACCUGAACAUGUCCUCAGCAGCACUGCAUGUGAUAGUUAGAAAGGACAUGUAAAAUAUUCUUAAAUAUGAUAUGUAUUAGAUAAAUUAUACAACUGCUAAAAAAGAAUGAGGCAGAAAAUGUGUUGACACAGAAAAGCUAACAGUAAGUGAAAAAGGUGAGCUGUAGCAUGUUGUAUAUGAUAUCGUAUGUAAUAUAUGUGUUGUAUAUGCCUUUAUAACCAUAAACCAUGUCUGGCAGAAUACACAGAAACUAUUAACAGAUUACCCAGGAGUGGGACUCGGGGGUAAGUGAGGUUAUAGAGAGAGAGGCUUACUUUUUGCUUUGUACUUUUUUGUAUUAUUUAAAUUAGAAACAAUUAAAACUAGGAACAUGAUUAUUUCAUAAUUUAAAAAAUAGGAGCCACGGGGUUAGUGAAUAAGCUGUUACGUGUCAUAAUGAACCCUCCUGUUUGUGUAACGAAUCCCAUUUACAGUAGUCUGUAGGCAGACAUUGUGAAGAAACUAGUAGUUCUUUCUUUCUCCUAUAUGCACCUAUAGGCCGGCAGAAAUAUCUAGCCCUGAAAAGUGAAAUGAAGCAUGCUUUCUGAAUGGUUCAUCAUUUACUGUUUCCUUCCAGUGAAUGGAAGAUUUUAACACAAAGGAGAGUUUGCAGGCAGAUGUUGAGAAGAAGCUAGUAGAAGCUUCCACCUUGUUAAUCUUUAUGUAUUUAUUUAGUUAUCAAGUCAUUUGUCUUGAUAUUAGUUCAUUUAAUUAUUUAAAUGAAUUAAUGCCUGUAAUGUAGGCAGAAGAAAAAAAUUCAAUUUUACCAUUAACUAAACAUAAUUUUGGAAACGCUGAGGGAUUUCCCAGAACCCAAAGCCAGCCUCUUGGCUCCUAGUGGCCCCGAGCAGCCCUGGUGCCCUGCAAACCCACCCACCAGCUGCCCCACAGAGGAUCUCUUCUCUCAAGGAGAGGGCCAUUGUUACUCCUCCCCACCAGGGAGGCACUGGGGAUCCUUGAUUAGGGUUUGGGGGAGCAGGAGGAGGUCCCAUUGAGGACACACACCAGACUUGUGCUGAGUAGGGGCUUGGGCCACAUGCAGCACUCUCAUGAGAUUUGCCAAUUCACCAAAGCAAACCCAGAUCAACACUUUGUUGCUCUAAUAGGGUGUUGUGACCUUCUUCUUCUAAUUGUUGAAUAUUUAACUGAUGUUAAAAAUGGUGAUUAUUGUUGUAAGCAAUGAAAACACAAUAGGCAUAUAAAUGGGAUAUGUUUGUAUGUCAGAUUAAAUAUAACCUAUAAAUAUGUCUCCCCAGCCCUGCUCUCUAAGAGAGAACUCUGUUCACAAUUGAGUCUCCUCCUGCUAGUAUUUCCCCGUACUCUUAGUACCACUCCUAUUACUCUCCUUUUUGUCCUGUCUGUCAAAGCAUACAAGUUCCCAGGUUCAGAAAUUUAAUUCUCCUCUUCCGUCAGUUCCCUUUCAUAGAAGCAGGUUUUCCAGUGAACACUCGAUUUCUUUAGUGCAAAAGUGAUCUGUGUCCUUUUUUGUAGAAAAUGUAGGAAGUAGGUUUAAGUAAAAGAAGAAAAUACAGCACACAACAGGAUUUGGGUUUCCAAGCUGCUGAAGUAGGAAGGGGCAUGCCAAAGUCUGCAGUUCCACUCCCUUGUCCCCAGCCAGACCCACCCUGGUGGCCAUCCCUGAAGCAAGAGCCAGGACCCCCAUCUGCCAGGCACCAAGAAGCACUUCUCCAUUGCCAAUUAAUUUUUUUUUCUUUUUGAGACAGAGUUUCGCUCUUGUCGCCCAGGCUGGAGUGCAAUGGUACAAUCUCAGCUCACUGCAGCCUCCACCUCCUGGGUUCAACCAAUUCUCCCACCUCAACCUCCCAAGUAGCUAGGAUUACAGGUGCUCGCCACCACACCCAGCUAAUUUUUGUAUUUUUAGUAGAGAUGGGGUUUCACCAUGUUGGCCAGGCUGGUCUCAAACUCCUGACGUCAGGUAAUCCACCCACCUUGGCCUCCCAAAGUGCUGGGAUUACAGGCAUGAGCCACCAUGCCUGGCCCACUGCCAAUUAAGUGUAAGGGGUGGAGGCCCGAGGGAGAACCCAAGGUCUAUUUGCCCUAAGCCAUCAAUGCCAGGGAUGGCUCCUUGCCCAGAACACCUUCCCAGAUGGACCAGUUAAUGCUUCUGGUGAUGAUGCCAUCCGAAUGCUAUACUGAAAGCCCUUCAGCCGAGGAUCAAGGUUCUGCUUGUAUGCACGGUUGUUGAAAUGCUAUUUAAAAGUGCCGUGCCGUGGUGUGGUGUGGGGACCUAGAGACCUGGGCUUUGGGGCCAACAGUAAGAAUUUGAAUCCUGCUGCUUCCACUUGUUAGUCUUGGGCUUGUUGCUUAAAUCUCUCUGCAAUUCACUGUCCUUGUCUGCAAAAUGGGAAUAAUUGUUGUUACAGCACUACUAGUAGUAACUGGGCUUAAUAAAUACUGAAUAGCUGUGGUCUCCUGUUAUUAUGAGUUCUUGAUCAUUACAGUAAACAUAUUUGUGUAUAAAAUUA